AAUCGCUCCGGAGCUUCUGGAGGGGGCAGAUGCAGGUGCCGGCUGCUGCAGUGCAGUAGCUGCUGGAGGCUGGGGAGGCCCGGACCCGGUGCAGGAAGACGCCGACCACGCGGGCUCCUGAUCGCGGGCGCCCACAGCGCGGACAUGGCGGGCUGGUGGCCGGCGUUGUCGCGCGCGGCCCGGCGCCACCCGUGGCCCACCAACGUGCUGCUUUACGGCUCGCUCGUCUCGGCCGGGGACGCGCUGCAACAGCGGCUGCAGGGCCGCGAGGCCAACUGGCGCCAGACGCGGCGCGUGGCCACGUUGGUGGUGACCUUCCACGCCAACUUCAACUACGUGUGGCUGCGCCUGCUGGAGCGCGCGCUCCCGGGCCGAGCGCCGCACGCCCUGCUGGCCAAGUUGCUGUGCGACCAGGUGGUCGGUGCGCCCAUCGCGGUCUCGGCCUUCUAUGUCGGUAUGAGCAUUCUCCAAGGAAAGGAUGACAUAUUUUUGGACCUGAAACAGAAAUUCUGGAAUACCUAUCUGAGUGGACUGAUGUACUGGCCCUUUGUACAGCUGACCAACUUCAGCCUUGUUCCUGUUCAAUGGAGAACAGCUUACGCUGGAGUCUGUGGUUUUCUCUGGGCCACCUUCAUCUGUUUUUCCCAGCAGAGUGGUGACGGCACAUUCAAGUCAGCUUUCACCAUUUUAUAUACAAAGGGGACCAGUGCCACAGAAGGGUACCCGAAGAAAUGAGAAGUCAAGGACUCUCUUAAAGGGACCACAUUUUUUACCUAAAAUGCACAGAAUUGCCUGCAGACAAAAUAUUUGAUGUGCCAAUUAUGCACUUCAUUUUGAGGAAUUACUACUAUUUAUAGACCCACUUUUUAAAAAAUUAUCAAUGAUUAUUUUUGAAUUGUAUUCAGACUUUUUUCCUGUUCUAGUCUGAAAUAUUACUUCUCUAAUAUUUUGGUUAAUAUGAAUAAUAGUGGCAAAAUGGCAUUUUAGAAUUAUUAAUAUUUCUAAUAUUUUAACACAAGUUUCAGGAAACUUGGUUUUGAUUGUUCACAUUUCUAUUCUAAAAUCUCAGGUUAUCUCCUGAACACUUUUGGGCAGAUGAAGUUUUAUACCAAAAAAUAGUUCUUAGAGUGAAUUUUAAUUUACAUAGAACUCAAUCGAAAUGAAGAUUUAAUAACCAGAUUUCUUUCUCCAAAACAUACACAAUUUGUUAUUUUAGUAAAUACCUUUUUUUUUUUUUUUUUUUUUUGUGGUGGAGUCUUGCUGUCUCCCCGGCUGGAGCGCAGUGGCACGAUCGCGGCUCACUGCAGCCUCCAUCCUCUGGGUUCAAGCAAUUCUCCUGCCUCAGGCUCCUGAGUAGCUGGGAUUACAGGCACGUGACACCAGGCCCAGCUGAUUUUUGUAUUUUUGUUCAUUUGCUUUUGUUUUUGACACAGAGUCUCGCUCUGUCGCCCAGGCUGGAAUGCAGUUGUGAGAUCUCGGCUCACUGCAAGCUCCGCCUCCCGGGUUCACGCCAUUCUGCGUCAGCCUCCCAAGUAGCUGGGACUACAGGCACCUGCCACGAUGCCUAGCUAAUUUUUUGUAUUUUUAGUAGAGAUGAAGUUUCACCGUGUUGGCCAGGAUGGUCUUGAUCUCCUGACCGCAUAAUCCACCCACCUCGGCCUCCCAAAGUGCUGGGAUUACAGGCGUGAGCCACCACAACCGACUUUUUUUUUUUUUUUUUUUUUGAGACAGAGACUCGCUCUGUCACCCAGGCUGGAGUGCAGUGGCAUGAUUUCGGCUCACUGCAACCUCUGUCUCCUGGGUUCAAACGAUCCUACUGCCUCAUCCUUCGGAGUAGCUGGGAUUACAGGCAGGUGCCACCAUGCCUGGCUCAUUUUUGUAUUUUUAGUAGAGAGGGCGUUUUGCCAUGUUGGCUAGGCUGGUCUCUGUCCGUCCUCUGAGCUCAAGCUAAGCCAUCAUAUCCCAGUGACCUGCACAUAUACAUCCAGAUGGCCUGAAGUUACUGAAGAUCCACAGAAGUGAAAAUAGCCUUAACUGAUGACAUUGCACCAUUGUGAUAUGUUACUGCCCCACCCUAACUGAUCAAUGUACUUUGUAAUCCUCCCACCCUUAAGAAGGUUCUUUUUAAUUCUCCCCACCCUUGAGAAUGUACUUUGUGAGAUCCACCCCUGCCCGCAAAACAUUGCUCCAAACUCCACCACCUAUCCCCAAACCUGUAAGAACUAAUGAUAAUCCACCACCCUUUGCUGACUCCUUUUUUGGACUCAGCCCGCCUGCACUCAGGUGAAAUAAACAGCCAUGUUGCUCAUACAAAGCCCGUUUGGUGGCCUCUUCACACGGACACGUGAGACAGUCUCCAACUCCUGGCCUCAACUGAUCCACUCUCAUUGGCCUCCCAAGGUGCUGGGAUUAUAGGCAUGAGCCACCGCACCUGGCUCAGUAAGUACAUUUUUUAUUAUCAAAAACAGAGUAGUGUAUGAUUGGCGUAUUCUGUGUAGAAUGUAUUUUAUUGAUGUCUUCUAUUUUUAUAAUUUUUAAUGAAUGCUUUUUAGUUUUGGGCAGAUUCAGUUGACUAAAGCACCUCAUUUCCCAGAUACAUGAAAUAAAAUACUUGGUUUCUUUUCCAAUUUCACACUGAUGUUAUUUUGUGAAAAUCAGUGCUUUAAGAUAAAUAUUUAUACUUUAAGGUAAACAUGAGAAACUUGAUCUAAUAUUUAAUAUUUAUUCAGUUCUACGCUUUAUUAACUUCUACACCAGCAGAUUUAAAAAUUAUGUAACUAUCUCAAGAAGUUUCACUUGGACGUAGUGGUUCACGCUUGUAAUCCCAGCACUUUGGGAGGCUGAGGUGGGAGGAUUGCUUAAGGCAAGGAGUUUGAGACCAGCCUGGGCAAUACAGCAAGAUCCCAUCUCUAUUUUAAAGAAAAGUUUCACUUUGGGAGGCCAAGGCGGUUGGAUCACAAGGUCAGGAGAUCGAGACCAUCCUGGCUAACAUGGUAAAACCCCAUCUCUACUAAAAAUACAAAAAAUUAGCCAGGCGUGGUGGUGGGCGCCUGUAGUCCCAGCUACUCGGGAGGCUGAGGCAGACGAAUGGCAUGAACCCGGGAGGCAGAGAUUGCAGUGAGCUGAGAUUGUGCCACUGCACUCCAGCCUGGGUGACAGAGUGAGACUCCGUCUCAAAAAAAAAAAGUUUCAGUAAAUUCCACCUAAGAAUUCCACCAGAGUUCUGUCAUCUCCAAUGUCAUGUUCCACAGAUUUCAAGUUGUGAAGCCCUGAACUGUUAAUUUAUCCUGAGAAUGUAUAUUUAAGCUUAAUUUAAGACUAUAUACCUAAAAAUUGAGCAUAUAAUUUGUAUAAUUUGUUUAUGUAAGUUUCUGUAAGUCAUAAAUAUGUAGUUUCCAAGUGGAUAAUUUACCUGAAUGUAAAAGGCAUUAAUAUAUUUUACAUUAUUGGGACCAUAGUACAGAAAUUUCUAAAUGGUUUGUAAAAUAACUUGUUAUUUGCUUUGUUGUAAAAGUAGUUAAUACAAUGGAAAAAUGGUUUCGUAAUAAGAAGAUACAUUUUAACAUCAAAACGUAGGCCGGGCACAGUGGCUUACGCCUGUAAUCCCAGCACUUUGGGAGGCCGAGGCGGGCAGAUCACGAGGUCAGGAGAUCGAGACCAUCCUGGCUAACAUGGUGAAACGCCAUCUCUACUAAAAAUACAAAAAAUUAGCUGGGCAUGGUGGCGGGCGCCUGUAGUCCCAGCUGCUCUGGAGGCUGAGGCAGGAGAAUUGCAUGAACCCGGGAGGCGGAGCUUGCAGUGAGCAGAGAUCAGGCCACUGCACUCCAGCCUAGGCGACAGAGCGAGAAUCUGUCUCAAAACAAACAAACAAACAAAAAACUGUACCCAAGUUAAUUAUAAGUACUACCUGGUGCAAAACUUUACAGAAGCUGUGGUAUCACUUUUAUGAUAGAAGAAUAGUGUUUGCAUUUUGUAUAAAAGUACUUGGGGCUGGGCAUGAUCGCUUAUGUCUAUAAUCCAAGUGCUUUGGGAGGCGAAGGCAGGUGGAUCAUCUGAGCCCAGGAGUUUGAGACCAGCCUAGGCAACAUGGCAAGAGCCUGUCUCUCCAAAACCUACAAAAAUUAGCCAAGCAUGGUGGUGUGAGCCUGUAGUCCCAGCUACUUGGAAGACUCAUGCAGGAGGAUCUCUCGAGCUCAGGAGGCAGAAGAUGAAUAAAUAAAUGGAUGCAACUGAAUGAGAUGAGGUCUCUCUUGAAGGAGAGAGCAAAAGAGAUUUAAAUAAUAACAAUUAUAAGAAGGCUGGGCGCGGUGGCUCAUGCUUGUAAUCCCAGCACUUUGGGAGGCCAAGGCAGGUGGAUCGGUUGAGGUCAGGAGUUCAAGACCAGCAUGGCCAACACAGUGAAACCCCGUCUCUAUUAAAAAUACAAAAUUAACCGGACAUGGUAGUGCGUCCUGUAGUCUCAGCUACUCAGGUGGCUGAGACAGGAGAAUCGCUUGAACCUGGGAGGCAUAGGUUGUAGUGAGCCGAUAAAUAUAAAAAGUAUUAAAGUACUAACAGAAGAAAAUUUCCACUGAUCACCCUUUAGCUUUAAAUAAUGCAGAAGCAUAUGCCCAGUUUACUUGUAAUUAAAAAUCAUGCAUCAUUCACAAUUUAUCAGUCUUUUUUGUUUGUACAAAAACUAAUAUAAGUUAUUCUCUUUUAUUUGUAUUGUGAUUGGUUUGAUGAGAGGGAAUUAGGCCACUUGAGAGUUUGUGCGUGUUUAUAAUUUUCUGGCUGGGCCCGGUGGCUCAUGCCUGUAAUCCCAGCACUUUGGGAGGCCAAGGCGGGCGGAUCACUUGAGCUCAGGAGUUUGAGACCAACUUGGGCAAUGUGGUGAAACCCUAUCCCUACCAAAAAUACAAAAAUUAGCCGGGUGUGGUGGCUUGCACCUGUCCUCCCAGCUACUUGGGGGUGCUGAGGCAGGAGGAUCACUCAAGCCCAGGAGGUGGAGGUUGCAGUGAGCCGAGAUCACGCCACUGCACUCCAGGAAGGGCAACAGAGCAAGACUGUGUCUAUAAAAAAAAAAAAAAGAAAGAAAAGUAAAUUAACUUUGGUAUUUCAGGUUGUAUUUAUAUGGGGACUUCACAUCAACUAUGUUCACUACAAUUGACCAAGUUAAGUGUAGACAGUCUCUUUAAUAGAGAGAUUAUCUGGAACUGCAAUUUUUUUUUUUUUUUUGAGACAGAGUUUCGCUUUGUAGCCCAGGUUGGAGUGCAGUGUCGCGAUCUCGCCUCACUGCAACCUCUGUCUCCCGGGUUCACGCCAUUCUCCUGCCUCAGCCCAAGUAGCAGGGACUAAAGGCGCCCGCCACCAUGACCCACUAAUUUUUUUUUUUUUUUGGAUUUUUAGUAGAGUCGGGGUUUCACUGUGUUAGCCAGGAUGGUCUCAACCUCCUGACCUCGUGAUCUGCCUGCCUCUGCCUCCCAGAGUGCUGGGAUUACAGGUGUGAGCCACCGCGCCCGGCCUGGAACUGCAAUUUCUAACUCAUACAUCAUUGCUAUAAACCUUAUUUGUUUACUGUUUCUCUUCCAAGGACGGUCAGUCAUCCUUUAAAAUUCAUUUGAAGUUAUGAAAAGAUAGUUUUUGUUACAUGGGCAAUUUACUUUUAGUACAGUAAAAUGUUAUGUGAAUUUCUACAGAAUGUUUGCUAGAAUGAAUUAUAUCUAGGAUAUGCUUAACAAUAUAUUCUGGAGGCAGCUUUCAUUUGAAAUUAGGUUCAUCUUCUGAGAGUAUUAAAAAGUUAAUGGGUUUUUGUGCCUGAAGAUUUUGAUGUUGCAUUUGGCUACAUUUAAUCCACUUUCACCCAUAAGGUUUAGCAUCUAAAAAAAUUAAAUCACUGCUAAUGCAAUUAAAAUGA